GCUGACUGCCCUGCUGUCGCCGCCUCAGCAGUCAGACUGGGAGGGCAGGCUUAUAUGGAGAGCCCUGAGGCCCAGGGUAGUUGGUUGGAGGAUGGAACUUAAGGUUUCAAUUGACUCCUGUCUGGCAAUUGCCCUUUUAGGGUCUCCUCUACCUCUGUCACCUGGGAGUAAACCUAAUCUUUAGGGAUCUGAGGGUCAACGUGAUCAACAGAUGAAACCGCCAGUUUAUACAGCAGCCCUGGGCCAAACUAGUCCCUUAGAGACCCUCAAUCCAGACAGGAACUAGGGCAGAGCCAAGCUGCUGGGGUCACAGGGCACUGAAGUGGAUACCCAUGCUGAUCUGCCUCCCAAGGCCUAUGAUGGCCACAGUGCUGUGCACAGCCACCUUGCUGCAUCCUGCUGUUGGUGGGCUCUUGUGCUCAGAACCCCAGGAGAAGGGCUAGAUCACACUGAUAAGACUGGCAGCUUUUUUUAAAAAACGACUUUCAAGGUUUGGUUAUUUUUAUCUCCAUGACCUCUGAUUUCCCUGUGGAGCAAAUGGUAAAGUAGGGGUGGGUGGAGAGGGACUUUGGCAGACUAUGGACAAGGACAGCCCUGAACAGCUGGCCCUGUCACAGGAACUGGAACAUGGUCGGAGCCAAGGACACAGGACUAACAGGAAAGGACACAGACUGCUGUCAGGACACAUACUACCACACACCCGAGGCCAGGACCCUGCUGACGUGGCAGACCUCCACCCUGGCCCCUUACUGCCCCCCGCCCCUCUCCCCCACCUGCCAGCUGCCAACAGGGCUCUGCCUUGUGUCUGCCACACCUGUCACUGCCUAUCCUUGUCCAGGGGGGGCCCCAUCAGCCCCUCCUCAGCUGCCCAGCAAAGCAAGCAGUUAGUGGGGAGGGGAGGGAACAUGGAGCGGGGGCCGGUGGUGGGGGCAGGACUGGGGGCCGGGGCCCGAAUCCAGGCACUGCUGGGCUGCCUGCUCAAGGUGCUGCUCUGGGUGGCCUCUGCCUUGCUGUACUUUGGAAGCGAACAGGCCGCCCGCCUUCUGGGCAGCCCCUGCUUACGGCGCCUCUACCAUGCCUGGCUGGCAGCAGUGGUCAUCUUUGGGCCGCUUCUGCAGUUCCAUGUCAACCCUCGGACUAUCUUCGCCAGCCACGGCAACUUCUUCAACAUAAAAUUUGUGAAUUCAGCCUGGGGCUGGACAUGCACUUUCUUAGGGGGCUUUGUGUUGCUGGUGGUGUUCCUGGCUACACGGCGCGUGGCAGUAACUGCCAGACACCUGAGCCGACUGGUAGUAGGGGCAGCCGUGUGGCGGGGAGCCGGCCGGGCCUUCCUGCUCAUCGAGGACCUGACUGGCUCCUGCUUCGAGCCACUGCCCCAGGGUCUGCUGCUCCACGAGCUGCCUGACCGCCGCAGCUGCCUGGCAGCCGGCCACCAGUGGCGAGGCUACACCGUCUCCUCCCACACCUUCCUGCUCACCUUUUGCUGCCUGCUCAUGGCAGAGGAAGCAGCUGUGUUCGCCAAGUACCUGGCCCAUGGGCUUCCUGCCGGCGCCCCACUGCGCCUUGUCUUCCUGCUGAACGUGCUGCUGCUGGGCCUCUGGAACUUCUUGCUGCUCUGUACCGUCAUCUAUUUCCACCAGUACACUCACAAGGUGGUGGGCGCCGCAGUGGGCACCUUUGCCUGGUACCUCACCUAUGGCAGCUGGUAUCAUCAGCCCUGGUCUCCAGGGAGCCCAGGCCAUGGGCUCUUCCCCCGUCCCCACUCCAGCCGCAAGCAUAACUGAAAGAAAUAAAAACCAUCGGGCCUG